AAGUGCCGUUUCGGUUUAAUCUAGUGUGUGACUGGGUCUGUGUGAGGGAGAGAGUGUGUGUGGUGUGGAGGUGAAACGGAGGCAAGAAAGGGGGCUACCUCAGGAGCGAGGGACAAAGGGGGCGUGAGGCACCUAGGCCGCGGCACCCCGGCGACAGGAAGCCGUCCUGAACCGGGCUACCGGGUAGGGGAAGGGCCCGCGUAGUCCUCGCAGGGCCCCAGAGCUGGAGUCGGCUCCACAGCCCCGGGCCGUCGGCUUCUCACUUCCUGGACCUCCCCGGCGCCCGGGCCUGAGGACUGGCUCGGCGGAGGGAGAAGAGGAAACAGACUUGAGCAGCUCCCCGUUGUCUCGCAACUCCACUGCCGAGGAACUCUCAUUUCUUCCCUCGCUCCUUCACCCCCCACCUCAUGUAGAAGGGUGCUGAGGCGUCGGGAGGGAGGAGGAGCCUGGGCUACCGUCCCUGCCCUCCCCACCCCCUUCCCGGGGCGCUUUGGUGGGCGUGGAGUUGGGGUUGGGGGGGUGGGUGGGGGUUGCUUUUUGGAGUGCUGGGGAACUUUUUUCCCUUCUUCAGGUCAGGGGAAAGGGAAUGCCCAAUUCAGAGAGACAUGGGGGCAAGAAGGACGGGAGUGGAGGAGCUUCUGGAACUUUGCAGCCGUCAUCGGGAGGCGGCAGCUCUAACAGCAGAGAGCGUCACCGCUUGGUAUCGAAGCACAAGCGGCAUAAGUCCAAACACUCCAAAGACAUGGGGUUGGUGACCCCCGAAGCAGCAUCCCUGGGCACAGUUAUCAAACCUUUGGUGGAGUAUGAUGAUAUCAGCUCUGAUUCCGACACCUUCUCCGAUGACAUGGCCUUCAAACUAGACCGAAGGGAGAACGACGAACGUCGUGGAUCAGAUCGGAGCGACCGCCUGCACAAACAUCGUCACCACCAGCACAGGCGUUCCCGGGACUUACUAAAAGCUAAACAGACCGAAAAAGAAAAAAGCCAAGAAGUCUCCAGCAAGUCGGGAUCGAUGAAGGACCGGAUAUCGGGAAGUUCAAAGCGUUCGAAUGAGGAGACUGAUGACUAUGGGAAGGCGCAGGUAGCCAAAAGCAGCAGCAAGGAAUCCAGGUCAUCCAAGCUCCACAAGGAGAAGACCAGGAAAGAACGGGAGCUGAAGUCUGGGCACAAAGACCGGAGUAAAAGUCAUCGAAAAAGGGAAACACCCAAAAGUUACAAAACAGUGGACAGCCCAAAACGGAGAUCCAGGAGCCCCCACAGGAAGUGGUCUGACAGCUCCAAACAAGAUGAUAGCCCCUCGGGAGCUUCUUAUGGCCAAGAUUAUGACCUUAGUCCCUCACGAUCUCAUACCUCGAGCAAUUAUGACUCCUACAAGAAAAGUCCUGGAAGUACCUCGAGAAGGCAGUCGGUCAGUCCCCCUUACAAGGAGCCUUCGGCCUACCAGUCCAGCACCCGGUCACCGAGCCCCUACAGUAGGCGACAGAGAUCUGUCAGUCCCUAUAGCAGGAGACGGUCGUCCAGCUACGAAAGAAGUGGCUCUUACAGCGGGCGAUCGCCCAGUCCCUAUGGUCGAAGGCGGUCCAGCAGCCCUUUCCUGAGCAAGCGGUCUCUGAGUCGGAGUCCACUCCCCAGUAGGAAAUCCAUGAAGUCCAGAAGUAGAAGUCCUGCAUAUUCAAGACAUUCAUCUUCUCAUAGUAAAAAGAAGAGAUCCAGUUCACGCAGUCGUCAUUCCAGUAUCUCACCUGUCAGGCUUCCACUUAAUUCCAGUCUGGGAGCUGAACUCAGUAGGAAAAAGAAGGAAAGAGCAGCUGCUGCUGCUGCAGCAAAGAUGGAUGGAAAGGAGUCCAAGGGUUCACCUGUAUUUUUGCCUAGAAAAGAGAACAGUUCAGUAGAGGCUAAGGAUUCAGGUUUGGAGUCUAAAAAGUUACCCAGAAGUGUAAAAUUGGAAAAAUCUGCCCCAGAUACUGAACUGGUGAAUGUAACACAUCUAAACACAGAGGUAAAAAAUUCUUCAGAUACAGGGAAAGUAAAGUUGGAUGAGAACUCCGAGAAGCAUCUUGUUAAAGAUUUGAAAGCACAGGGAACAAGAGACUCUAAACCCAUAGCACUGAAAGAGGAGAUUGUUACUCCAAAGGAGACAGAAACAUCAGAAAAGGAGACCCCUCCACCUCUUCCCACAAUUGCUUCUCCCCCACCCCCUCUACCAACUACUACCCCUCCACCUCAGACACCCCCUUUGCCACCUUUGCCUCCAAUACCAGCUCUUCCACAGCAACCACCUCUGCCUCCUUCUCAGCCAGCAUUUAGUCAGGUUCCUGCUUCCAGUACUUCAACUUUGCCCCCUUCUACUCACUCAAAGACAUCUGCUGUGUCCUCUCAGGCAAAUUCUCAGCCCCCUGUACAGGUUUCUGUGAAGACUCAAGUAUCUGUAACAGCUGCUAUUCCACACCUGAAAACUUCAACGUUGCCUCCUUUGCCCCUCCCACCCUUAUUACCUGGAGAUGAUGACAUGGAUAGUCCAAAAGAAACUCUUCCUUCAAAACCUGUGAAGAAAGAGAAGGAACAGAGGACACGUCACUUACUCACAGACCUUCCUCUCCCUCCAGAGCUCCCUGGUGGAGAUCUGUCUCCCCCAGACUCUCCAGAACCAAAGGCAAUCACACCACCUCAGCAACCAUAUAAAAAGAGACCAAAAAUUUGUUGUCCUCGUUAUGGAGAAAGAAGACAAACAGAAAGCGACUGGGGGAAACGCUGUGUGGACAAGUUUGACAUUAUUGGGAUUAUUGGAGAAGGAACCUAUGGCCAAGUAUAUAAAGCCAAGGACAAAGACACAGGAGAACUAGUGGCUCUGAAGAAGGUGAGACUAGACAAUGAGAAAGAGGGCUUCCCAAUCACAGCCAUUCGUGAAAUCAAAAUCCUUCGUCAGUUAAUCCACCGAAGUGUUGUUAACAUGAAGGAAAUUGUCACAGAUAAACAAGAUGCACUGGAUUUCAAGAAGGACAAAGGUGCCUUUUACCUUGUAUUUGAGUAUAUGGACCAUGACUUAAUGGGACUGCUAGAAUCUGGUUUGGUGCACUUUUCUGAGGACCAUAUCAAGUCGUUCAUGAAACAGCUAAUGGAAGGAUUGGAAUACUGUCACAAAAAGAAUUUCCUGCAUCGGGAUAUUAAGUGUUCUAACAUUUUGCUGAAUAACAGUGGGCAAAUCAAACUAGCAGAUUUUGGACUUGCUCGGCUCUAUAACUCUGAAGAGAGUCGCCCUUACACAAACAAAGUCAUUACUUUGUGGUACCGACCUCCAGAACUACUGCUAGGAGAGGAACGUUACACACCAGCCAUAGAUGUUUGGAGCUGUGGAUGUAUUCUUGGGGAACUAUUCACAAAGAAGCCUAUUUUUCAAGCCAAUCUGGAACUGGCUCAGCUAGAACUGAUCAGCCGACUUUGUGGUAGCCCUUGUCCAGCUGUGUGGCCUGAUGUUAUCAAACUGCCCUACUUCAACACCAUGAAACCGAAGAAGCAAUAUCGAAGGCGUCUACGAGAAGAAUUCUCUUUCAUUCCUUCUGCAGCACUUGAUUUAUUGGACCACAUGCUGACACUAGAUCCUAGUAAGCGGUGCACAGCUGAACAGACCCUACAGAGCGACUUCCUUAAAGAUGUCGAACUCAGCAAAAUGGCUCCUCCAGACCUCCCCCACUGGCAGGAUUGCCAUGAGUUGUGGAGUAAGAAACGGCGACGUCAGCGACAAAGUGGUGUUGUAGUCGAAGAGCCACCUCCAUCCAAAACUUCUCGAAAAGAAACUACCUCAGGGACAAGUACUGAGCCUGUGAAGAACAGCAGCCCAGCACCACCUCAGCCUGCUCCUGGCAAGGUGGAGUCUGGGGCUGGGGAUGCAAUAGGCCUUGCUGACAUCACACAACAGCUGAAUCAAAGUGAAUUGGCAGUGUUAUUAAACCUGCUGCAGAGCCAAACCGACCUGAGCAUCCCUCAAAUGGCACAGCUGCUUAACAUCCACUCCAACCCAGAGAUGCAGCAGCAGCUGGAAGCCCUGAACCAAUCCAUCAGUGCCCUGACGGAAGCUACUUCCCAGCAGCAGGACUCAGAGACCAUGGCCCCAGAGGAGUCUUUGAAGGAAGCACCCUCUGCCCCAGUGAUCCUGCCUUCAGCAGAACAGACGACCCUUGAAGCUUCAAGCACACCAGCUGACAUGCAGAAUAUAUUGGCAGUUCUCUUGAGUCAGCUGAUGAAAACCCAAGAGCCAGCAGGCAGUCUGGAGGAAAACAACAGUGACAAGAACAGUGGGCCACAGGGGCCCCGAAGAACUCCCACAAUGCCACAGGAGGAGGCAGCAGCAUGUCCUCCUCACAUUCUUCCACCAGAGAAGAGGCCCCCUGAGCCCCCCGGACCUCCACCGCCGCCACCUCCACCCCCUCUGGUUGAAGGCGAUCUUUCCAGCGCCCCCCAGGAGUUGAACCCAGCCGUGACAGCCGCCUUGCUGCAACUUUUAUCCCAGCCUGAAGCAGAGCCUCCUGGCCACCUGCCACAUGAGCACCAGGCCUUGAGACCAAUGGAGUACUCCACCCGACCCCGUCCAAACAGGACUUAUGGAAACACUGAUGGGCCUGAAACAGGGUUCAGUGCCAUUGACACUGAUGAACGAAACUCUGGUCCAGCCUUGACAGAAUCCUUGGUCCAGACCCUGGUGAAGAACAGGACCUUCUCAGGCUCUCUGAGCCACCUUGGGGAGUCCAGCAGUUACCAGGGCACAGGGUAGGAGCAACGGUGGGAAUGCCCUCUGAGGAAUGCAGUGAUGUCCAUCAGUCACCUCUCACCCAGAGCCUGGCAAAUUCAGUCUCUUUCACAGAACCUAAAGCCAAGCCAGGUUCAGUGGGAAAUCCCACCUGUCCAAACACUGUGUGAGACACCAGAAUUAGAGGCCUGCAAGCCUGCUUCCUUCAUCCCCAAUGCCCAGAUGGGACAGGUCACCAGCCUCCUGUGUCUACCCCCACCUUUCUUGCUUGCUGGCCUCCUCUCUCUGCAGUGCCUCUCUCAUCCCUGCAAUCCAGACAGCACAUGCAGCAGCUCAAGUUAUCUGAUCACACAGAACAGGCCUGCCAGUUGGGCAGCUGCAGUCAUGGUUUCUGCCACACGAGGGCGCUGCUGGCCAAUUAAAACUCAUGCCCCUUAGCAGACAGUUUGGGGAUGAGGGCACCCUUUCUCCAAAACAGGGGUCAGAAACUCUGGGGCUCUCUGGGCCCCAGAGAGCAUGGGCCCAAAAAGUGAGACAAAUAUUUGGUACCACUUGUUCUUCCUUGAAAAUGGCCUGAGACCCCUAAACACUUUGCUCUAGUGGCCUGACAUCUCAAUGUGCUUCCAGCUGAACUUGGGAAGCCCCCUCUUUCCAGGCACUUAACACCUUGCACAGGUGCAUCUCUCCCUUAAGGUGUAGCAGGUUCCAGCUGUAUGCCCCGUUGUCCCCCUGCCUUAAUGGCAGUCACUUUCCGACCCAGAUGGUGGAGGUGCCUGUGGUUUUUAGGGGGAAAAAAUCUCUUAUAAUUGUUCUAAGAAAAGUGUUUUGUUAGUGAGAAAGUGUUAGGGGUGACUGAAGCCUGGGAGAGUUAGUCUCCCCGUCACCUACUCCAGCACAAACCUAUAGAAUUCAAGAUGGUCUAGUGGAUGUUUGCAGCCUCAGUGGCUGGAAUACACCCCAGGACAUUCCAGGGCCCUGAGCCAAAAAUGGUGUCAGAAAGCUGGAUAGGAGUGUGGGCUGCUUUGGGCCAUGAGCCUCAUACCCACCCUGUAUCAGGCAGUGUUUCUGCUAGGGGUGCCAAAUGGCCCUGGGGCCUCUAUGGGACUGAGGACUCCACAAUUGACCCUCCAUCUCCAUGAAGCCCUUCCAGGCUGAACAGGCUAAGGGACAUGACAGAGGUUCUCCUCCUCCUUCCUACCCCCAUGCCUGAGGGCCCCUCCCCAGGAGGACAGCUUGAUUAAACAGUCGGUGCUGCUGGAAUUACUGCACAGCUGGCGCUCCCCCCAGCACCCCGAGCAGAGCAGCAGUGCAGAUUAAAAUCUCCAAUUAGCGUUAAAGUGAAGUGAGGAGGUGCUGAGGCUGCCAAGGAGGCCAGACGGGGGCCCUGGGUUGGCAAAACCCCCACUCUUGCCUGGAUUCUGAGUGUCACCCUUAGUCACCCCUACUUUCCCAGCUCCUCUCCCAACAGCUUUCAGUGCCCAUUAGUUUUGUAUCGCUUGGGGCCAGAGGGCUUUGCAGAGGGGUGGAAGGGGGCAAAUGCCUUACCUAAAAUGCUAGGGACACCGUAAGUAUGGAGGAGGAGAGCGGUCAGUGCUCAUCAAGGGAGAUACCCUAUUCACUGCCUGCCAGGCAGCCAGGCCAAGGUGACUUCACGCUACAGCUCUGCUUCUUCUUUUUGCUUGAAGAAAAGAUAAACAGGACGGGUCCUUUCAGGUCCUUUACCUAUGAAGUGCUAGGGGACAUGGUGCCCACAUGAACAUCUCUCUCUGCAUAUUUUAUCCUAUCUGACCCAUCUGCUCCCACCGAAGUUAUGGCUCCUUCCUCCCUCUCUCCAUUCUUCUCUCAGCUUUCCUGUGGGCAGGGGUAGGCACAGCCAGGCUUGGGAGCAUCGCCAUGCCCUGCCACCUGGGUCCCAGCCUGCUCCUCGUUAUAGUCUUCCCAGUUUGGGGAAGAGCAGUGAUAUGCCAAGAAUGGAGGCCUCAGACUCUCCCAAUCCCUGAUUUUUACAUGUCCCCCUAUAAGGCCCCUCUGCCAUCUACACUUUUGCCCUUCAUCCACAAAGCCCAAAAGGAAGGCAUUAUAGCUAGCCAUGCCCUCUGACUGCCCUCUGCCCCUUUAAGGGAAAUGGAAAUGGGUACCCAGCUGACUGAACCUACUCAACACCUCCAGAAAUUAGACACUAGGGCAUGGUGCCACCCUCCCAGGCUGGCACAUGCUACCCUGGCAGAGGAUCAAAUAACCCCCCCAUCAUACCCUGCCCCAUGUCUUCCUCUACUCUCUCCCUCAUGCUUUCUCUCUCUCUCUCUCUCUCUGUCUCUCUCUCUCUCUCUCUCUCAGCUCAAAGCACAGCUGAGCCUUAAAAGGGGGGUUGAGGGGGUGGAGAGACCAAGCUGGGGCAGGGGGGUAUAGAGCUCCAAUAGCACGUUUUCACCUGCCAUUUAAUUGGAUGUAUUUUUAAUUAAUGGGACCUCAGGGACCAACAUGAGACAAUCUGAUAUCUGAAUAGGGACAGGGGAGGGAUUGGGUAAGGGAGGAGGAUUGGGCCACUGGGUGCGGUUACCGGGAACCCAGGCCCAUCAAUCACUGGCCACUUUGCGUUCUGGCAUGGAGAAUAGCGAGGUGGAGGAAGGGAGGCACUGGGGAGAGGUGCCAGGAUUUCCCCCCAACUGCCAGGACCUCCAAACGGAUUGGAACUAUACUGGUUGACUCAGGUCUGGAGCCCAAAAUCACAGCCAGAAUAUAAGAUGUGAAAAACAAGACCCAGAGAGGGGAAAUCAUUUGAAUCCUGUCCUGGUAUUGCUUUGUGUUCCUGGAUUUGGAGAAUUUCUGGGAACACAGGAAAAGGAAAGCCAAUUCCAUUCCUGGCUACCUCAUCCCCUCCAGUCUGAAAGGACGUGUGAAUGCCACCAGGAUCUGAACCCAAGAUUCCAGCCUCGGUCACCACCCUGACCCUGAGAAUGCCACUGGGAUGGGGAGAACUUGUCAGUCUUCAUCCUUCCCCACAAGUAUACUGAAGCCAGGACAGCACCUGCCUUAGAGAGCUCUUAGAGGGAUUAUCCGCAGCCUGAAGAAAGAAGGUUACAACUGAGGAAGAACUUCUGAACAGGGAAGAGUGGAAGAAAAGACUGCAGUACGUAGAGCAUCAAGGGAAGCUGUGGAAAUAUAUUUUCUUAAGUACAGGCUCAGCUCCAGAAGCAGACCCAGAAUGGCAUCCUUCUCUGAGACCCAGACCCCAGCCCCUUUUCAUGGAAGACCAGCACAAAGGAGGAAGUAGGUUAGGGAAUGGUAAGGCUCCAUGUGAUGGGACUAAUGUGGAGAGGCCUGGGGCCUUUCCCUGAGGACUGGAUGGCUGGAGUUUGGGAGCCUGAGUUGACAGAGGAGGCUAAGCCCGGGCAGCUACUUUGUUCCAGAAAUCUAAGGUCCCUGGAGGGAGGCUCUGCUUUGGGAGGGGGAAGGGAGCUAACAUUGCAGAGCACCAACUGUGAACCAGGUACAAUGGCAGAGCCUUUCCAUACCUGUACUCACAACUAGCGGGUGAGGAGUCAAGGCAAAUAGGUGUCUCAUAGCUCCCCAUAUCUCGGCAGUCGACCACCUCCUCCUUUGAUUCUCUGAUGUCACUGCCAGUUCUCCUCCUAUUGCUCUGACCUGUCUUUCUCUGUGUCCUUUGCAAACUCAUUCUCAACUCCUUAGACUCAGUCAAGUCCCCCAGUUACACACUUCCAUGGUACUAUAUAUCAUUCCUUCAGAGCACUUAACACAGUUAUUUCCUAUGUAUUUGUCCAGUCAUUUGAAUAAUGAUCCUAGUUUCAUUGGAUGGAAAGUUCCACAAGGUCAGUGACCAUUUCUAUCUGUGUUCACCAAUGUGUUCCCAGUGCCCAGAAACAAUGCCUAGCAUAAAGCAGCUGUUUUGUAAAUACUUGUUCAAUGAAUGAAUAAAUGACAAAAGAACAUC